AGUCCAGUGAGGAAUAACUGUAGAUAAGAUGAGAUGAUGGGCAUUAAGUGUAACUGCUGAGAAGCCUUCAUAGAGGGAAAGGUGAUAAGAACUGAGUUUUUCUGGCAUGAGGAGUUUACCAGGCAGGAGAGGUGGAGACGCUAGGCUAGGCAAAUAGGCUGCAGCCAUAGUUCUGCUGAGAAACAGGUUUUGAACCAAGGCAACUCCAUCUGGAGAUAUGUAUCAGAAAGAUUAGGAGAUAGAAUCUCCAUCUUGGUCACUUAUUUGGUCUUCUAAGACAGCAAUGGGACCGUCUCUUAAAUACUGGAGUUGUCCUAUCUCCUUGGGCUGAUACCCUGAACUGUCAUUUGGCGCGUGAGGCGGGCAGCGCGGUUGAGGCCGAAGAGCUGGUGAAGGGCAGCCCGGCGUGGGAGCCGCCUGCCAACGACACGCGGGAAGAAGCCGGCCCACCAGCGGCUGGGGAAGAUGAGGCGUCGUGGACGGCGCCCGGUGGCGAGCUGGCCGGGCCAGAAGAGGUGCUGCAGGAGUCGGCUGCGGUGACCGGCACCGCCUGGCUGGAAGCUGACAGCCCAGGCCUGGGAGGAGUGACCGCAGAGGCGGGCAGCGGCGAUGCCCAGGCCCUUCCAGCUACGCUCCAGGCUCCCCACGAGGUCCUCGGGCAGUCAAUCAUGCCCCCUGCCAUUCCUGAGGCUACAGAGGCCAGCGGGCCACCCUCCCCCACCCCCGGCGACAAGCUGAGCCCAGCUUCUGAACUCCCCAAGGAGAGCCCCUUGGAGGUUUGGCUGAACCUGGGGGGCAGCACACCCGACCCUCAAGGGCCAGAGCUGACUUACCCAUUUCAGGGCACCCUGGAGCCCCAACCGGCAUCAGAUAUCAUUGACAUCGACUACUUCGAAGGACUGGAUGGUGAGGGUCGUGGCGCAGAUCUGGGGAGCUUCCCAGGGUCACCAGGAACCUCAGAGAACCACCCUGAUACUGAGGGAGAGACCCCUUCCUGGAGCCUGCUUGACUUAUACGAUGAUUUCACCCCCUUCGAUGAAUCUGAUUUCUACCCCACCACAUCCUUUUAUGAUGACUUGGAUGAAGAGGAGGAGGAAGAGGAGGAUGACAAAGAUGCAGUAGGAGGUGGAGACCUAGAAGAUGAAAAUGAGCUUCUAGUGCCCACUGGGAAGCCUGGUCUGGGGCCCGGGACAGGCCAGCCCACCAGUCGGUGGCAUGCUGUCCCUCCACAGCACACUCUGGGGUCGGUCCCCGGCAGCAGCAUCGCCCUCAGGCCCCGCCCAGGAGAGCCAGGCAGGGACUUGGCCUCCAGUGAAAAUGGCACUGAGUGCCGCAGUGGCUUUGUGCGGCAUAACGGCUCCUGCCGGUCAGUGUGCGACCUCUUCCCAAGUUACUGUCACAAUGGCGGCCAGUGCUACCUGGUGGAGAACAUAGGGGCCUUCUGCAGGUGCAACACGCAGGACUACAUCUGGCACAAGGGGAUGCGCUGCGAGUCCAUCAUCACCGACUUCCAGGUGAUGUGCGUGGCCGUGGGCUCGGCUGCCCUCGUCCUGCUCCUGCUCUUCAUGAUGACGGUGUUCUUUGCCAAGAAGCUCUACCUGCUCAAGACGGAGAAUACCAAGCUGCGUAGGACCAACAAAUUCCGGACCCCAUCUGAGCUCCACAAUGAUAACUUCUCCCUCUCCACCAUUGCCGAGGGCUCUCACCCAAAUGUAAGGAAACUUUGCAACACUCCCCGUACCUCCUCCCCCCAUGCCCGUGCCUUGGCUCACUAUGAUAACGUUAUCUGUCAGGAUGAUCCUAGUGCUCCCCACAAAAUCCAGGAGGUUCUCAAGUCCUGCCUGAAAGAGGAGGAGUCAUUUAACAUCCAGAACUCCAUGUCGCCCAAACUUGAGGGUGGCAAAGGUGACCAGGCUGACUUGGAUGUGAACUGUCUUCAGAAUAAUUUAACCUAAAGCAGAGCAAGAAGAGAGGAAGCGGGGGUAGUGGGUGGGGGGUAGGGGAAGAAACAUUAUCUCCUCUUGUACAGAGUCUAUUUCUUGUAACCAUUUGUUAAACUCUUUUCUUUUUCUGAUCUCAUGGCAUGCUUUUAUGUAUUUUGUACAGGAGGCAAAAAAAUACUUAAAAUAAGCAAAGAAACUGAACAGAAUUGCAUACAUUGGGUUGUUUUUUCUGUGCUGUCUGUACAUUGCUUCUGCUGCUGUGAUUUCUAAACCUGUGCUGUUAUUCAACUGACUUUUUUUUGUACUUUGACCCACGUUUUUUUGAAAUACCAGUAAAAAACAAAGUUCUUGAAAUAAAACUUUUUAAAAAGUUA